GCAUUUCGACUCAGCCCGCUGAACGCCUGGAAGAAAUUUUGCAGACCCACCAGAGAUCCCCAGAUUCCACUUGUAAAACCAUUGAUCUAAAAACUACGUCUUGACUUCAGAACACUUCUUUUGAUCUGGAAUUAUCUAUUAUUGACCACAGAGAGCAGCCACUGACGAUUUCCUGGAACAGGGCCCUGUAUAGAGAGAGGCCUCCUGGGAUGGAUGUCACCCGCUUACUCCUGGCCACCCUGCUGGUCUUCCUCUGCUUCUUCACUGCCAACAGCCACCUGCCACCUGAGGAGAAGCUCCGAGAUGACAGGAGCCUGAGAAGCAACUCCUCUGUGAACCUACUGGAUGUCCCUUCUGUCUCUAUUGUGGCGCUGAACAAGAAAUCCAAACAGAUCGGCAGAAAAGCAGCAGAAAAGAAAAGAUCUUCUAAGAAGGAGGCUUCGAUGAAGAAAGUGGUGCGGCCCCGGACCCCCCUAUCUGCGCCCUGCGUGGCCACCCGCAACAGCUGCAAGCCGCCGGCACCCGCCUGCUGCGACCCGUGCGCCUCCUGCCAGUGCCGCUUCUUCCGCAGCGCCUGCUCCUGCCGCGUGCUCAGCCUCAACUGCUGAGCGCCCCCACUCCCGGCCGCGAGCAGGCAGGGCUUCGGGGACGCGGGGCGCUUCUCGGGCGGGUGAUCCCUAACAGGGCGGCUUCCCAGGGCUGCAGGCGGGCGGAGGUUCCAGGAGAUGGGACUUCAGGGAGACCUGGCUUGGGCUAAAAUCGAAAUACAAUAUAUAUAGGCUGCU